UCAGUGUGCCUAACAAUUUAUAACACGUAAAAAAUAAUAAAUAUUAGGUAACUUUACUUUGUAAUAACAGGCCUUAGCAUAAUAAUAGCAGAUAUUUGAUACUUACUAUACAUAGUACCUGGCACAUUCCAUGUCUUAAUUCAUGUAACUAUCAUAAUAAUCCGAUGAAGAAGGCACUAUUAUUAUGCUCAGUUCUUCUAGAGAGGAAGAGUCUGAGGCAUGGAAGGUUAGGUAACUUGCACAGGGUCACACAGACAGUAGGUGAUGGAGUCACAAGCCCUCUAUGCGAAUCAGCUACAAAAUUGAGAAUUUCUCUUUUAGAAUCACUGCCACCAUCACUGCCUUCAACAAAUACAUGGCAGAGCUGCAUCCCACUUAGAAGUUAUGAAAUUGGGGCCAGAUUAUUUUGAUACAUACCACAUUUUGAGAUACACUGCCAAAUUAAGAGGCUAAAAAAAUUACAUCUCCUGAGUAUUUAAUGUUCCUCCCUAUAUAAGUAUUAUACUAUUUUAAUUAUUAUAGCUUUAAAAUGUGGUUAAAUAUCUAUUAAUAUUGAUUAGGCCAGAUACCCAAUGGUGAAGAGAAGAUAUAAUUGAAAUUCAUAAACUCAUGGAAGGGAGAGGCAUUUAGCAUAUUCACCAAACUCUAAUAAUAAUAUAAUGAAUAUGUUAAAAAUAGAAAUCUUUUAAAAAAUUUGCUGUGAAUCCUGAAAACUAAACUAUAAAUUCUAAAAUUUUGAUAUAAUUAUUGGGAAAUUUUUAAUUAAAAUAAUGCUUGCAGCCAGGCACGGUGGCUCACACCCGUAAUCCCAGCACUUUGGGAGGCUGAGGCAGGUGGAUUAUGAGGUCAACACAUCGAGACCAUCCUGGCCAACAUGGUGAAACCCCGUCUCUACUAAAAAUACAAAAAUUAGACAGGCGUGGUGGUGGGUGCCUGUAGUCCCAGCUACUCGGGAGGCUGAGGCAGGAGAAUCACUUGAACCCUGGAGGCGAAGGUUGCAGUGAGCCAAGAUAGCGCCACUACACUCCAUCCUGGCCACAGAGUGAGACUCCAUCUCAAAAAAAAAAAAAAAGUGCUUAGUUUUAUAAUUGUAAAUUAUAAAUAUUUAAAAAUUCUACUCAAACUAUGAUCAAAUACAAAAUUACUAUUAACAUAUUGGUAUAUUUCCCAUUAAUCUCCUCAUGAAAAGUUAUUUUUGUUUUGCUUAUAUACUUAUAUUCACACUAUUUAUAUACCUUUACGUCCUAUGUCAUUUAACAUAAAAUUUAUAAGCAUUAUUUCUUAUAUUCACAUGCUACUUAAAAUUACUUUAAUAACUGCAUAAGAUGCCUACUUCUGAGUUGUAAGUUAAACAACUACAAUUAUGAUUAUUUUGACUAAUCUCCUACCUAGGUGUUUAGGUUGUUUCCAAUUUUGUACAUUUACGAAUGAAACUGGAAUUCAUAUUUGCCUCACCCAGUUUCAGGAUUAUUUCCAUUAAAAAAAUUCCCAGAAGUAUAACUGCUAGAUCAAAUGCAACUCUUUAUAUCAAUAAAAAUUAUUGAAUUAUCCAUUUCAAAAUGUUUGGCAAUGUAUUUUUAAUACAUACUAAAAACAAAUAAAAUGUUUUAUUUCUUAUUUUGUUUAAUCUUCUACUCCUAUAUCCAUAUUAUAUUUUAGCUAGUACAGUGUAGCUUUAAAAUAUGGUUCAGUGUCUACCAUAGCUUGUGUAAUUCAUUUCUCUUCCUUUCAAAAUAUUCUGUGAAUUUUUGUGUGUUUUUAAUCUUCCAGAUAAACUUUAGAAUGAUUUUAAGUCAGAAAAUCAAACUUUCAUUAUGAUUUUUACUAAAAUUGUGUCAAAUCUAUAAUUUGGAGGUAACUGACAUUUGGAAGUAUUAUUUUUGAUAUAUGGAAACAUAGUUUGUCUAUUAUUUAUCUCUUUUUAAUUCUUUCAAAGCUUAAUCACUUUUUAUUCCUAUAGGUCACAAAUAUUCCUUAGUAAAGGUAUUCUUAAAGUUUUGUUGCUAUAGUGAAUGUGCUUCUCCUUUCAUUCAUUUCUUAACAGCUUUGAGGUAUAAUUUACAUAUAAAAUUUAUAGUUUAAGUAUAUAAUUCAAUGAUUAUUUUUAGUAAAUGAGUUGCUCACUUGCACCACAAUCUAGUCUUAGAAUGUUUCCAUCACCACAAAAGGAUUUUACCUUCUGUUGGUGGUUUCUCAUUUAUCUGUUACAGUCAAAGAACGUACUUUAUGUGAUUUUAUUCCUUUUAAAUCUAUUCAGAUGUGUUUUAUGGCCUAGAAUAUGGUCUAUUUUGGAGGACAGUCUGUGUGUGCUUGUGAGGAAUGUCUAUUCUGCUUUUGUUUGGUGGAUAGAGUUGGUGGAUCAGUAGUCUGCUGAUCGUGUUGUGUAAGUGUUAAGUGAUACAAAACAUAUCCUUGCUAAUUUUGUAUCUAGUUGUUCAUCAAUUAUCGAGAUUGGGGUGUUGAAGUCUCCAAUUAUUAUUGUCUAUAUCUCUCUUUAGUUCUGUGAUUUAUUGCUCCAUGUACUUGGGGAAAUCUGAGGUAUAUAUAUAACUUUUCUAUUUUCCUGUUGAAUUAACCCCCUUAUCAUUAUGAAAUGUACUCUUUGUCUCAAGUAUUUUAUUUAUUUUUGUCUCAAAGUGUAUUUUGUCUAAUAUUAGUGUAUUCACUGCAGGUCUUUAAUGGUUACUGUUUGUAUGAUAUAUCAUUUUCCAUCCUUUUAACUUUCAGACUAAAUUUUUGAAUCUAAAGUCUGUCUCAUGGCAACCUGUGGUGGCUCAUGCCUAUAAUCCCAGCACUUUGGGAGGCCAAGGUGAGUGGAUCACCUGAGGUCAGGAGCUCAAGACCAGCCUGGCCAACAUGGUGAAACCCUGCCUCUAUCAAUAAUACAAAAAUGAGCCAGUAUGGUGGUGGGCACCUGUAAUCCCAGCUACUUAGGAGGAUAAGGCAGGAGAAUCACUUGAAUCCAGGAGGUGGAGGUUGCUUGGAGCCAAGAUCCCAACACUGUACUCCAGCCUGGCUGACAGAGUGAGACUCCAACUCAAAAAAAAAAAAAAAAAAAAAAAAAAAAAAAAAAAAAAAAAAAAAAAGGGAAAAGCAAAAGCUUGUCUCUUGUAGACAGAAGAUAGUUGGAUCUUGCUUUUCAAAAUCCAGCCUGACAAUCUCUGCCUUUUGGUUGGAGUAUUUAAUCUAUUUACUCAUAAUGAAAUUACAUCUUAACCAUCCCUAAUCUGAAAAUCCAAAACUGAAAUUCCCCCAAAUCCAAAACUUUUUGAGUGCUGACACGAAGUCACAAGUUGAAAAUUCCACACCUGACCUCAUAUGAUGGAUCACAGUCAAAAUGCAGAUACACAACACACAGUUUACUUAAUGUCUCCAAAGAGACCCUCCCAGCCCCCUUCAGCUGUGAAGUAUCUUUUCCACACAUGCCCCAGACUUCGUCAUGCAGGCACAUCCACAAAGGGUAAUAAAAUGGCACAUGUCAGGCAAGACACACCAAUGGCGGGUUGCCUGUGAUGCCCUACAUGAGGCCAAGACCUACAUGCCUUACUCAUUAUGUUGUUUUGUUUUGCUUAUUCUCUUCUCUGUGGUAUAAAGGUAUUGUGGAAAAUGUAGAAAGAUCUGCAGAUACCCUUAUGAGUAACAGUAGUAAAGAAAAGAGGAAGCAUUUAUACUUAUCUAUAGCACAGAAAGUCAAGCUGUUGAAGAAACUGGAUGGUGGUAUAAGUGGAAAAUGUCUUAUAGAAGAGUAUAGUGUUGGAGUGACCACCAUGUAUGACCUGAAGAAAGAGAAGGAUACAUUGUUGGAAGUUCUAUGCUGAAAGUGAUGAACAGAAGUUAAUGAAAAAUAGAAAAGCAAUGCAUGGAGUGAAAUAUGAAGUCCUUGAAUAUGUAUUGAAAGAAUGGAACCAUCAGUGUCACAGUGAAUACAUGCCACUUAAUGGUAUGCUGAACAUGAAACUUGCAAAGAUCUAUCACGAUGAACUGAAAAUUGAAGGGAACUGUGAACAUUCAACAGGCUAGUUGCAUAAAUUUAAGAAAAAGCACAGCGUUAAGGUUUUGAAGAUUUGUACCAUUUCCUGAUCAUGAAGCAAGGGAGAUAUUCACUGAUGAGGUUACUAAGGUCAUCACUGAUGAAAAUCUGAUACCAGGACAGGUCUGUAAUGCUGAUGAAACAUCACUGUUUCGGCAUUAUUGCACCAGAAAAACACUGACUACAGCUGGUGAGACAGCUUCAAUAGGAAUUAAGGAUGCUAAGGACAGAAUAACUGUUCUGGGAUGUGCUAAUGCAGCACGCAUGCAUAAAGAAAACCUUGCUAUGAUAGACAAAAGCUUAUAUCCUUGUUGUUUUCAAGGAGUAAAUUUCUUUCCAGUAAAUUAUUAUGCUAACAAAAAGGCAUAGAGAAUUAGGGAUAUCUUUUCUGAUUGGUUUCACAAACAUUUGGUACUAGUGGCUCUUGCUUGCUGUAGGGAAUCUAGACUGAAUGAUUAACGACUGCAAGAUUUUGGCACUGCUUGAUAAGGAUUCUGCUCAUCAUCCAGCAGAAAUUCUCAUUAAAAAUGUUUAGGUCAUGUAUUUUACCCUAAUUGUGACUUCAUUAAUUCAUCCAUGUGACUAGGGUGUUCUUGGAUCAAUAAAGAAUAAAUAUAAAAAGUUUCUUGAUCAGCAUGCUAGCAACAGUGAACAGAGGCAUGAGUGUGGAAAGUUUUCAAAAGGAGUUUAGCACGAAGAAUGCCCAUGUUUGGAAUACAGUGACAAAUACACAGUUGUGCAUGCCUGGCACAACCUCUGGGCUAUAACUAUGUUCAGUGAUGGUGAUGAACAAAGUGGUGACUUUGAAGGUUUCUAUAUGUCACAUGAGAAAAAAAAUAAUGUCUGACCUCCAUACAUAUACAAAAAAAUACACCUUCAGAGUCUGGCAGUAAGAUGGAAGAAACAGAUGUCAUGUAAGUUUUUACCAGCAAUAAUGCGGCUCUAAUUAUUCAUUCAUUGAUCCAUGGGGAAAUAGCCAAAAUGGUUCUUAAUCAAGGUGAUUAUGAUAAUAGUGAUGAUGAAGAUGAUGUUAACACCGUAGAAAAAGUGCCUAUAGAUGACAUGGUGAAAAUGUGUGAUGGGCUUAUUGAAGGACUACAGCAGUUUAUUUAGUAUCCCCAAAUGGGUUAAAACAUGGAUUUUUAGAUUUUAAAAUGCUGGGCUUCACCCUCAGAGUUUCUCAUUCAAUAGAUUUUGGUCAGGGGACAAGAAUGUGUAUUUCUAACAAGUUUCCAGGUGAUGAUGAUAUCAUCCUGGGAUCCACACUUUACAAUUCAAUGACCGAGUAUAUUUAUUUUUAUGAGAGAAUGUGUAUUACUUGAUUUCAGUUUAUUCUCAAUUACACAAAAAAUAAAUGAGGACACUUAAUAUUUUGAAAACAUAAGAUGGAAGAAUGUAUAGCUAUAGCAACACAUCUAACUAAACUAUUACUCAGUAACCAAAAAAACUCAAUAGAUUCUCCAAAGCACAAAUCAAGAUGUCCUUUGCUGAACUGUAUGAAGUUUCUGUGUUUUAUUUUAAUUAACUGACAUGCUAAGGACAAACAUUUUCUCGAACUUAUUUGUUCUAUAAAUUGUUAACACAUGAGUUUAAAAAUAUUUAUAUGGUAAUAAUUAUCAGUCAUCUUUUCUUUUGAUUACUGAUUGCUUUUGUGAUUUAAAAAAAUAUUUUUCUAUCCCGAGAUUAGAUAUUCACCAGCAAUUUCCUGAUUUUUGAUUUUGUCUUUCUUUACAUAUAUCACUUUGGUCUACCUAGAAAUUAUUUUGAUGCAUGUAUAUUUUACUCAAUUUUUAACUAAAAUAAAUACAAUUAUUUUUAUACAGAAAAUUCUUUAGGCAUACUAUAUUCAGGGCAUUGCAGUAAAUACUCUCAGUGUUUAUAAUUAUCUUUGUAAGAUGCAUAUUAAAACAGCAAACAUUGUUGAAUUCUCCAAGUUAGUUUUAUUUUAUAGCAUGAGGUGGUAUAAUCUUCUUAAGCAUUCCUGGAAAUAUUUUUUUAAAAAAAAUCACAAACGUAUCACACAUAUCUAAAAUUAAGUGUGCCAACUAUAUACCUUUGAUGUUUCCUGAGAGUCCUGAGUUUGCAAAACCUUACCUAUAUAGCAACAUUCAACUGUGUACAAUUUUAUGAAUCAGGCAUCACAUUUUCCACGAGUCCACUCCACAGAAAUGGCUUCAGUCCAUUUCAUCAAACUGCUAUGUUGUGUCAAUAAGCUUUCUAUGCACUAUUCCACUUUUAAGAACUGAUGGCCCUUGUACAUUUGGGUUUUUUUCAACCAACAGUUGCAUGCUAAGAACAUCUUCCAAAUUCUGUUAGAAGACUGAAGAGGAACUUGGUCAGUUUUUCAGCAGUCAUCCAUGUCCUCUUGUUCUCAUUUCUGUUUUCUUCCUCCAAAAAAAAUCACUUCCCCUAUCUUUGGCUCAUUUAUUUUUCUAUGGUAUAUCACUGCCUAGCAUUGGAGUUGUUUUAACUUUUUCCUUCACCUAGCAUUACUUAUCAACAUGAUAGUUACAUUCCCAAAAACUAUAUUGUAAAAGAAAGCAGGGAUGAAAUAUUUAAGACCUGAUAGGAAAAGCAGGUUUAGGAGAUCAGAGUUAUAGUGAAUCUAAAAUAAAGGCUGAUGGCUCAUUAAAUAAAUCAACUAAUGGCAUUUUAAAUAUUUUUAAAUAGAAAAAAUUGGCAUUGUUCAAUAACUAGUAUUCCUUCUUCCUAACAAACUUUUUAUUUCAUUAACCUACUAAUCAUCUAAGAUUCUUAUGAAUAUGUUUUUCCUUCUUGUAAAUAAAAAUUGUUAUGAAAUAUUUUUUCUUGGAUCUUCAUGAAAUGAAAAAUGCUUUUAAGUUUUAUUAUUCAAUUACCUUAUUUAGCCCUGGAAAAUUGAAGAAGAAAAUGCCAGUGCACUGUGAUAUAGUCUUAAAAUCCUUCUAAAUGCAUUGUUUUAUAUUCAAAAGAACUUAAUGCCAAGGCAUAAAUGACCACAGCAGAGCACUGCUCUACCCUAAAGGUUUUACAUCCCAAUUCCUUUCCUUUGGCUUAUGUUGUCUCAGUUUUCUAUAUUUCUCUCAAGGUUACGUUACAAAAUUAUCUAUACAUACUUGCUCUUCCAUAUAUUUUACCUCUUCUUCUCAGGGCCCUAUGUUUUGCUGUAAUUUUAAAAAUUAUCUUCAAGAAAAAUUGCCCAAUUUUUACAAACAUAGUAUCCUAAAUUCCCACAUUUGUGAAAAAAGUAUAAAUAUGUAAAUACACAUAUGUAAAAUUUUGUACAGUAGGAAUGUUCAUUGGGGAAACGUUACUGAAACUGACACAAAGUGUUUAACAGAAAUUUGCUUAAAGGGAUCAAAUUUCACCUGGCAUAGGAACAUAUUUAAAACAGUGGGGUUGACACAAUAGCUACAUCUGUGUAACCAAACCAUCAAGGCUGACAAACUAAAUCCAGUUGUUAGUAAAGUUAAUGACUAAUUCUGAUCAAUACAUGGCCAAAAGAAAAAGAAAACACUGUAUCAUAAGAGCUGAAAAACAUCUACUGGGAAAUGACUAUUUUGUGAAUACUUAAAAGCCUUAUAAAUGUACUAUUAUAUUUUCACUUUUUCUAAAGUAUUAUAAUUGGCAGGGCUCAAAUUAGUAAAGUUAAAUAUAUUUCAACAUUUUAUUAAACACUGAAAAUAUUUUAUCCAUAUCAAGUAUCAGGGGCUUAAAAUGAGCUAUUCCAAAAAAAAGUAUCUCUCAUCAAUACUUUCACUUUAAAAGAAUUAUUAUAAUUUAUCCAUAUAUGAAAUACAAAAAUUAUUAGAACAUGUAUUAGGCUUAAAUUGAUUACAAAUAAAAAACAUUAAUCUUGCCUGUAAUCCCAGCUACUCAGGAAGCUGAGGCAGGAGAAUCACUUGAGCCCGGGAGGUGGAGGUUGCAGUAAGUGGAGACUGAGCCACCGCACUGCAGCCUGGGCGACAGAGUGAGACUGUCUCAAAAAAAAAAAAAUUAAUACGACAACACAAUAAUAAAUAAAUUUAGCUCAUCACAAGGGAGCAUGGUCAUUAAAAUGAGUUUAGCAGAAUAGUCAAUUCAAACUUAUUUCCAAAGACUAACAGUAUAAAUUAUAGGCAGUUUGAGAUUUAAAAUGUGGCAAACCAAAAAUAGGGCAGUAUAAAGGCUACAGAGACUCAACUACCAAUGAAUGACAAAGAAAAACUGGCCCAAUAGUUAGUCAAAAUGUGACUAUUAGUACUAUUAGGCUAAAAUUAAAAGUAUUAAUAAGUCUAUUGAUUAUAGCAAAUAAACCGCCAAAAAGCUCUAACAACUAAGACCCCUUUAACAGCUGAAUCAACUUAAUUCUUCUUAGACAAAUGCUUUUUGCCACAAAUAUUCAUUAUACAUCCAUUUACAUAUUAUGUUCUUAGAAAAUAAGAGAAAAAAAUCAGAAAAGGAGGCUUCCACAUAAUAAUAGGAAUUAUUUUUGAAAGAAAAUCUGACGUGGGAAUCCUAAUCUAAUUACUGUAUCAAAGUCAACCAAUUCUUGGUUGAAAGUAAACUACAGUAUCAUUUCAUAAGAGUGUUUACUGAUGAAAUUAGCCAGGAUAAAUUGUAAUGUUAACAGCCAUAAUAAAUAAAUGUCAUAAAAUACUAAUUACUUUUAGUCAACAAAAUAAGGUUAUUUAACAACUGUCUUAGUCCAUUUAUUUUUCUAUAAAGGAAUACCUGAGGCUGGGUAAUUUAUGAAGAAAAGAGGUUUACUUGGCUCACAGUUCUGUAGGCUGUACAAGAAGCAUGGUACCAGCAGCUAUUUCUGGUGAGGGCCUCAGGCUGUUUCCACUUGUGGGUGAAGGUGAAGGAGAACCAGCAUGUGCAGAGAUCACAUGGUAAGCGAGGAAGCAAGACAAAGCAGCAAGAAAAUCGAUAGGAGGGAGGUGCCAGGCUCUUAACAACCAGCUCUGACAGCAACUAAUAGAAAACUCACUCAUUAUCACUAGGAGGGCAUCAAGCCCUGUGUCAGGGAUCCACCCCCAUGUCUGAAAACAUCUCCCAUUAAGCCCCACCUCCAACACUGGGGAUCAAAUUUCAACGUGAGAUUUGGAGGGAUCCAACAAACCAAAUGAUAGCAAUAAUGCUCCCAAAAUACAGCAGGUAUAUGAAAUAUAGCAUUACUAAUGAAGUGUCCUUUACAUCUUCUCUGCCUGCUUCAUUAGUGAAUUUAUUACAAUAAAGUUUAAAAUAAGGCAAAGAACAUUCACCUUUCGGGCCAGGCACAGUGGCUCACGCCUGUAAUCCCAGCACUUUGGGAAGCCGAGGCAGGCGGAUCACGAGGUCAGGAGAUCGAGAUCAUCCUGGCUAACACGGUGAAACCCCGUCUCUACUAAAAAUACAAAAAAUUAGGCCAGGCGCGGUGGCUCACACCUGUAAUCCCAGCACUUUGAGAGGCCAAGGCGGGUGGAUCACCUGAGGUCAGGAAUUCGAGACCAGCCUGACCAACAUGGAGAAAACUGAUCUCUACUAAGGAAAAUACAAAAUUUUAGCCAGGCAUGGUGGCACAUGCCUGUAAUCCCAGCUACUCAGGAAGGCUGAGGCAGAAGACUCACUUGAACCUGGGAGCAGAGGUUGUGAUGAGCUGAGAUCGCACCAUUGCACCCCAGCCUGGGCAACAAGAGCAAAACCCCGUCUCAAAUAAAUAAAUAAAUAAAUAAAACAAAAAAAUUAGCCAGGUGUGGUGGCACACGCCUGUAGUCCCAGCUACUCAGGAGGUUGAGGCAGGAGAAUCGCUUGAACCCGGGAGGCAGAGAUUGCAGUGAGCUGAAAUCUGGCCACUGCACUCCAGCCUGGGCGACAGAGCAAGCCUCCAUCUCAAAAAAAAAAAAAAAAAAAAAGAGAAAAAACAACAAAAAAACAAAACCAUGCACCUUUCCCUGAUUUAAAUGAUUCAUCAGUAAUUAUCCAAAUACAUGGUACUAGCCUAUUAGGGAAAUACCAUGGUUUUAAGACAGUUGUUCUCAAUCUUUUUUUUCUUCUUUUCACGAAGGCCCAUUCAGGCUAGAGCAGAGAGGGGGAAGCUUACAUCCAGUAAACAAAAUAGCAGUGAUUUAAAUAAAACUGAGACCAGAAAACCGACUGCUUUCUACAUUUUAGGAACUGAUUAUCAUAAACAUAAACUUAUCUAACAAUAUCUGUAUUUCUAUUUGUAGCAAGCACAAAAGUUACAGUGUGCAGCACACUUUAAUCACUGCGUGAUUUAAUUACUGUGUCAAUAAAGGCAGUGGCACAGUCAGAAUUUGACAGAAUUGAGAAAAGUCCUGCUGAAAAGAUGAGACAAGUUCUGAGAUGAUCAUUUUUUAUAAUGUAAGCACUGUGUACAUUUAUAAAUGGCACGGUAGGGAUGGGAGUGGGCUGGGGGUAGAGAAUUCCGUAAAACAAGGGAACUUGAGGAAAUGCAAAAGACUGAAAAAAACCUGGCAUCUUCCAAAGGGUAAAAUUAGUAUGAUUGUUUAAACUAUUUUGUCCUUAAUUUUAGUCAUUUCUAAUUUAACAGCUAAAGAACAAUUACUGUAUAAUAACUGAAAUAUUUAGUAUACUUGGUAUUACAGCACCCUCUAUCACAUGAUCAUAUACAGAAUACAUUUCUAUGAACUGGUUGCUUUAAUCUGUGAACAUUUAUGUAGCUCUCUACUGGUUCUAGGGUUUAGUUUACUACUUCCCAUCCACGGAGUCAAAAGGACUACUAACUUGUGCAGGCUUAGUAUCACCAGUAUAUUUUAGUACCGUCUGUCCUGCAACAGCAAAAAGCAUUAUUGACAAAGCAAUCCUGAACUCUAAAUUAUUCCAGGUGUGGUCCUAGUACCAACAGCAUCAGAAUCACCUGAGAUUUUACUAGAGCUACACUAAUCCAGCUGUAUCCUCAGACCUUCCCUCCCAGUUAUAACCUCUGGUGUUGAGGCCCAGCAAUCUGUUUUAACAAGCCUUCUAGAGAAUCUGGAUGCAUGCUCCAGUUUGAGAAGCAUUACUAUAGGAGAAAUACAAUCAAAGAGUCAAGUUAACAUGUGCUAUCUAAACUCUAAAGGAAAUUUGUUUCAUUAUAUAUUUUGAUAUCCACAGCACCAUUCCAAUAAAACAUUUAGAACAACUCUGUUAGUACUCCAAGAUUACAGGAAAAAAAGAACAUUAUUAAAGGAAAAUGUGUUGAUUUUACUAACUUUGGGGAAAUUACUUUUCCUUUCUCUGAUUAUCUAAAAGAAACGUGACAUGCAAACGAAUCUACAUUGAGCAUUUCUGAGGCUACCUUUCUGAAACUUCCAUGGCCUAUUUUAAAGCAAAUUACUACAUUCUGCUUCUCGAUGGGUUCCUAACAUACACAGCAGGCUUUUACAACAGCGCUUUAAUAGGCCAAAGGAAACAAAAGCUUUUACAGCAGAGGCCAAUGUAAGCCACAAAGCUCGUGUCAUCUUCCUACCAGGCAAUUAAUACAGGGUCCCAGUCCUCAAAGAUUAAAGAACUGAUACGGGGAAGACUGAGAAUGACCCAGCAACAACGCAUAAGGAAGCAAAAAAUAAAAGGACGCCGUUUCUUCUGGACUUAAAACUAGAGAAAGAACAGUUUCCGCUCCAUUUUGGGUUUGUAAAGCUCCUCCUACAGGCAGCUUCCGCUUCAGAGUCGCCACAAAGUCCCUCCCGCGCGGGAACUCGGCGGGGCGGAGACUCGGGUCCCUCCCCGUCCAGGGCGGGAGAAAGGAAAGCAGGGGCCACGGUUUCUCUGGAAGGUUCCGAGAGAAGGGCGCGUGCCACCUCCGCGGGUGGCGGGAGACUCGGCACCAGAUGGCGCUGCCGCACCGAGAGCCAGAGCCUGGGCCGCUGGGGAGACGGGAAGAGGCGUCACCGGAUCCCUUCCUUUGCGCUCGUUGCCGGAAAUGUGCGCUGCAACCAGCCUCUGGUCCCGGAUAUUAAGACUUCUGGAGGGUUCCCGCGUGAGGGCGGGGCCAGAACCGGAACCGAACGGCGACCGACGAGCCCCGGAGCGGAAACCCGGGGCGGCGCCAGCGGGCCCUGGUUGCUGGAUUCUAUAAACCUGGAGAGUAAUCCUAAGAAAAAUCAUCAGAAGAAAGGAAUUUGUAGAACUAAAACUGCAAACAUCCAGAAUCUUGAUGGUGUGCCAAGCCAAAUGUCAACUGGAACUCAACCAAAAACUAAAGUGCUCUCUGAUAACAGACCCAAAGAAAGAGUGGAAAUUGAGGCAAAAGAAGCAUGUGACUGGCUCCGUGCUGCCGGGUUCCCGCAAUACGCUCAGUUAUAUGAGGAUUCACAAUUUCCCAUCAACAUUGUGGCUGUCAAGAAUGAUCAUGAUUUUCUUGAAAAGGACCUUGUAGAACCUCUUUGCAGACGACUAAAUACGUUGAACAAGUGUGCCUCAAUGAAACUUGAUGUGAACUUCCAAAGGAAAAAGGGUGACGACUCCGAUGAGGAAGAUCUUUGUAUCAGCAACAAAUGGACUUUCCAAAGAACCAGUCGCAGGUGGUCUCGUGUGGACGACCUCUACACGCUGCUCCCUCGAGGAGACAGAAAUGGGUCACCGGGAGGCACGGGGAUGAGGAACACGACCAGCAGUGAGAGCGUCCUCACAGACCUGAGCGAGCCUGAGGUCUGCUCCAUUCACAGCGAAAGCAGUGGAGGCAGCGACAGUCGCAGCCAGCCGGGCCAGUGCUGUACAGACAACCCGGUCAUGCUGGAUGCCCCACUCGUCAGCAGCAGCCUCCCACAGCCCCCCAGAGAUGUCCUCAACCACCCCUUCCACCCCAAGAAUGAGAAGCCCACGAGGGCUAGGGCCAAAUCAUUUUUGAAACGCAUGGAAACACUCCGAGGGAAGGGAGCCCACGGGAGGCAUAAGGGGUCUGGGCGGACAGGUGGCCUGGUGAUCAGUGGGCCCAUGUUGCAGCAGGAGCCAGAGUCCUUUAAGGCUAUGCAGUGCAUCCAAAUACCAAAUGGAGAUCUCCAGAAUUCGCCGCCACCUGCCUGCAGAAAAGGGCUCCCAUGCUCUGGCAAGUCGAGUGGCGAGAGCAGCCCGUCGGAGCACAGCAGCAGCGGGGUGAGCACGCCCUGCCUGAAGGAACGCAAGUGCCACGAGGCCAACAAGCGCGGGGGCAUGUACUUGGAGGACCUAGAUGUGCUGGCGGGGACAGCACUGCCGGAUGCAGGGGACCAAAGCCGUAUGCAUGAAUUUCACUCCCAAGAGAAUUUGGUGGUGCAUAUUCCCAAGGAUCACAAACCAGGAACAUUCCCCAAGGCACUUUCUAUUGAAAGCCUCUCUCCCACAGAUAGUAGCAAUGGGGUUAAUUGGAGGACCGGUAGCAUCUCCCUGGGCAGAGAGCAGGUCCCUGGUGCCAGGGAGCCCCGGCUCAUGGCGUCCUGCCACAGAGCCAGCCGAGUCAGUAUCUAUGACAAUGUCCCUGGCUCCCAUCUGUAUGCCAGCACAGGAGAUCUUUUGGACUUGGAGAAAGAUGACCUUUUCCCUCACUUGGAUGACAUUCUGCAGCAUGUCAAUGGGCUCCAAGAGGUAGUCGAUGACUGGUCCAAAGAUGUCUUGCCUGAACUGCAAACUCAUGAUACAUUGGUUGGGGAACCUGGCUUAUCCACCUUUCCAUCUCCUAAUCAGAUCACCUUAGAUUUUGAAGGUAACUCUGUCUCAGAAGGUCGGACGACACCCAGUGAUGUGGAAAGAGAUGUAACAUCUCUUAAUGAAUCUGAGCCUCCUGGGGUCAGAGACAGGAGGGAUUCUGGUGUAGGGGCCUCUCUGACCAGGCCAAACAGGCGACUCCGAUGGAACAGUUUCCAGCUGUCGCACCAGCCCCGGCCGGCCCCAGCAUCGCCCCACAUCAGCAGCCAGACGGCCAGCCAGCUGAGCCUGCUCCAGCGCUUCUCACUGCUCCGCCUCACGGCCAUCAUGGAGAAGCACUCCAUGUCCAACAAGCACGGCUGGACAUGGUCAGUUCCAAAGUUCAUGAAGAGGAUGAAAGUUCCCGACUACAAAGACAAGGCUGUCUUUGGCGUUCCUCUCAUAGUCCACGUCCAAAGAACGGGACAGCCCCUGCCUCAAAGUAUUCAGCAAGCACUGAGAUAUCUACGCAGCAACUGCCUCGAUCAGGUGGGUCUUUUUCGCAAAUCAGGAGUGAAGUCUCGAAUCCAUGCCCUUCGCCAAAUGAAUGAAAACUUCCCUGAGAACGUCAACUAUGAAGACCAGUCUGCUUAUGAUGUGGCGGAUAUGGUGAAACAGUUCUUCCGGGACCUCCCUGAGCCUCUUUUCACCAACAAGCUCAGUGAGACCUUUCUCCAUAUCUAUCAGUAUGUCUCCAAAGAGCAGCGGCUGCAGGCCGUGCAGGCUGCCAUCCUGCUACUGGCCGAUGAGAACAGGGAGGUCCUGCAGACGCUCUUGUGUUUCCUGAACGACGUCGUCAACUUGGUGGAAGAGAAUCAGAUGACGCCCAUGAACCUGGCAGUGUGUCUGGCCCCCUCCCUCUUUCAUCUUAAUUUAUUGAAGAAAGAAAGCUCUCCACGAGUCAUACAGAAGAAAUAUGCCACUGGGAAGCCAGAUCAAAAGGACCUCAACGAGAAUCUGGCAGCAGCUCAGGGGCUAGCGCACAUGAUCAUGGAAUGCGACAGACUUUUUGAGGUUCCACACGAGUUGGUGGCCCAGUCUCGUAACUCGUAUGUGGAGGCUGAGAUCCACGUGCCAACCCUGGAAGAAUUGGGGACACAGCUGGAGGAGAGUGGGGCAACUUUCCACACUUACCUGAACCAUCUCAUCCAGGGCCUCCAGAAAGAAGCCAAGGAGAAGUUCAAAGGAUGGGUCACGUGCUCCAGCACGGACAAUACAGAUCUUGCUUUCAAAAAGGUGGGCGACGGGAACCCGCUGAAGCUGUGGAAGGCUUCUGUGGAGGUGGAAGCACCCCCCUCAGUGGUCCUGAACCGCGUGCUGAGAGAGCGCCACCUGUGGGACGAGGACUUUGUGCAGUGGAAGGUUGUGGAAACUCUAGACAGGCAAACAGAGAUCUACCAGUAUGUGCUGAACAGCAUGGCUCCCCAUCCUUCCAGAGACUUUGUGGUUCUCAGGACCUGGAAAACUGAUUUGCCCAAAGGAAUGUGUACCCUGGUGUCCCUCUCCGUGGAGCAUGAGGAAGCCCAGCUCCUGGGUGGUGUGCGAGCAGUGGUGAUGGACUCGCAGUACUUGAUAGAACCGUGUGGCUCUGGCAAGUCAAGACUGACUCACAUCUGCAGGAUAGACCUGAAAGGUCACUCCCCAGAAUGGUACAGCAAAGGCUUUGGACAUCUGUGUGCAGCAGAAGUUGCCAGGAUUAGAAACUCUUUCCAGCCCCUCAUUGCUGAGGGCCCAGAAACUAAAAUCUGAGUUUUGCCCAGUGUGACAUCAAACUCAGGGAAGAGGAAGCUAAAGUGACGAGUGUGGCAGAGAGUGUGCAUGUGAGAAAGCGAGAGAAAGAGGAACUGAAGGACGCGGUUAAUGCCUAAAAAUGGAAACGUUAAGAAGUUGGAAUGUUGGAGAUGCAAGAAUUUCCAAGAACUUUCUUAGCCUUCCUGGAGAUGGCUACAUCCCUACUAAUAUAAUUUUAAAAUGAGAACUUUAUAUAUAUUACUUAAAAUUAAAUGGACUAUUCCUUGUGCAUUGCCUAAUUUGCUAUUUAAAGGCUUCUAAGAAGCGUAUACCUAACUGUAAAUAAAUGUAUGUAUAGCAUAUGUACAUAUGUGUGUAUAUCUCCAUCUUUACUGUAUAUAUGUAAAAUACCAAUUUUAUAUAGAAUUGUGUGUUUUGAAAAUGACGGUGUCUGACUCAGUGAGUCCCUUCCUCACACAGUUCUUUCCAAGUGGCUCUGGGCCCCAUCUCUCCACUGUCCUGUAAGCUGUGCAGAACCUGCUGCUAACACCAAGGUGUGAACAUGCCCUGAUGCCUAACCAAAGAUGAGUUAACCAAAGGAAAAUAACAUUAAAGGAGACUUAUGUGUUAACGCUUUGUUUCUGCUAUUCAAAAACUGAGAGUGGAGAUCUGGGAUAAAGCAAGGAAAUAAUAAUUACUCCUCCUUAAAGCAAAUGGGGGGGUGAGAAGUCAUUACCAAAUUUAAAGCUAGAUGAGGAGUUGCCACUGGGCCCAGUAAGAUGGAAUUUCAGUGAGAUAUGGACCACCGGAGUCAGCGAGAGUGACUGAAACAGAAGCGAUACCUCUCGCUCCCAUGCCCAUCACUACAGACCCCAAGUCAAGAUGAAUAUCAUAGCCUUUACUUCUUCACAGCCAAAGGGAGCCCCUGUGUUGUCUCAAGUUUUUAUAAAUACAUUUCAUAAUGUUAUUAAAUGUCAUUCUAUUUGACCAGUGGCCUAUUUGGUCACAGUUAAUUGGUGUUUUCUUAUUGCACUGAAUUCAACUCCAGACACCAUACAAAGGGAGAUGAUGGCCAUUCCGUUCAAAUCCUAGAUCGUUACAGCUUCAGGGAAUUCAUAUUUUGUUAUGUGUAGGAUACUCUUAAAAUGUAAUUCAUUAAACUUUUACAAUCUGAAAGACAGGGUUUUUAACUAACAUGAGACCAAAACUAUGUUCUUUGAUUAGUUUUAGAUAGUAUAAUCGGGUUUAUUAAUUCUUCUGUGUUUCUUCACUAGCCAGUCCAAGCUACCUAUGCAUUUGACCCAACCUUAUUUAUUAUUGUACAGAUGAAGCGAAUUGACUCCCUUUAGCCAACUGCUAAUGGAUCGAAUGUGCUUUUUAUUGUAAUUCAACAGCUAUAGAGAGAAAGAUAACUUAUUGUGUGUUUGAUUUCAGGGAGAGAGAUUUUCUUUGGUCAUCCAUAAUAGAGAUUGAUAAGAUUUAGCAACUGGUGUUGGAGAAAAAAAGAAAAGCAAAUGAGUGUUUUCAGGUUUUUUUGCAUUAUAUGCAUUUAUGUAAUGUUUCUGUUAUCAGCAAUGUGCAAUUAUUUUAUUGAGAGGAAUAAAAAAGCUUUCUAUGAGUUUGGUAUGGUGCGAGGAAAAUCUUACAGUUUGAAUUAUGACCUAGAAAUUUUUCAUUCCCAUAUCUACCUAAGAAGGAAGCAGUAAAUCCAUAAUUUACCUUUUGGGCAAUGCUUUGUGAGCAAAACAAAGUCACUUCUGCCAUAACAUCUUGAAUUUAACCAUAUAUGCCAGAUUACUUUAUAUGCAUCAACAAGAUCACCAGUGAAGUUUAAUCUAGCUAAACACUGGUCCUGCUCCUGAGAUGGGAUCCUAUGUGUUUGGAAAACGUGAUAGGCACACGAGGAUGAGUGGCUUUGUAUCGCCCAGAGAGGUGCUUGUCCAGAUUUCACAUGCACAUGAAUUGCCUGGGGAUCUUGUGAAACUGCAGACUCUGCUCCAAGUAAUCUGGGCUGGGCCUGAGAUUCUGCAUUUCUAAGGAGUCUCAGGGAUGCCUAUGCUGCUGGCCUAAAACCACACUCAGAAACGAGGACCUAGAAGAUCCCUAAAACAGAAUAAGAACAAAUGUGAUUGUAUUUCUGAUUCUCCCUCUCUUCGAAUUAUCUGACUUUUUUGUUUUUGUGCACAUAGUAAUCAUAUCACCGCUGCAUAACAACACAGUGCAUCUUUUUAAAACAAGGAAAAGGGAAAAAAAGGAGAAAAAACGAUGCAUCAAGCUUGUUUGUCAAAUACCACAGUAUUUUAUUCAUUGUUAUCUUGCCAAUGGAAAUAAAGUAUGAUAUUGCAUUUAAAUAUUAUAUUUAUACCUCAUGUAUAUUUUUACCUCAAUUGUUGAUAUCAAUCAUCAAUUGUAAAUAAAUAAUUGCCAAGGCAAAUAAAUUUAUAUAUAUUAAAUAUUUCCUAUUUUCUAUAAAA